AGUGCCGAGUUUACCUCUGCGCGCGUCGGGGUUGGUGGCGGCGGCUGCGGCGAGUUCCUGAGGGGCGCCUGCGGGGGGCGUCCGCUCCGAGCGCCGAGGAGCCGAGCGGAGGAGGCGUCCCAGGGACACGCAGGGGAGGCCGGCCGGCCUGCACGGGGCGCUCCCGCCUCGGGGGCCCUGUCUGGCGCCUCAGCGCGCGCCCCGAUGGUCACCUGCGCCCACCUGGGCCGGCGCGCGCGGCUCCCGGCAGCUCAGCCCUCUGCCUGCCCAGGAACCUGCUUUUCCCAAGAGGAGAGAAUGGCUGCUGGGUACCUGCCCCGCUGGUCCCAGGUUGUCUGGUCGAGUGUUCAGCUCUCAGCAGAGAGGAGGCCUAGGAGAGGGUGGCUCCUCUCCACAGGCAAGUCAUUCGGACGUCUCUGCAGGUCUCUGAAGCUCUCAGCAGGGACGGUAGCUCCUCUCUGAAGCUCUCAGCAGGGAUGGUAGCUCUUCUCUGCCGGCAGAUCAUCUCUGCAGCCUUCAGUGGAGAGGGUACUCCUCUCUGCAGCUGGUCGUCCGGUCCCAUCCUGUCAUCUGUCUGCCUUCUUUGUCCUCUGGCCGUCCUCUGCCCUGCUAAGCCUGAGCCCAGGGCUUUUACGGACCUCAGAGGGGAGGAAGUGUGUGCCGACUGGUUCAUGGGCGGCCAUGGGAGGGUCGAAAGAGGCACCAUGAGUCCCCACUCUGGUCUGUAGGACUGGCAGCCUGGCCCCCAGUCUUCAGGCCCUCCCUGGCCUGAAGGUGGGGCCUUACUGGGGACCCACCCCCUUCUGCCCAGGAAUUAAUCUGCCUCCUGCUGCCAUUCACGGCCCUAGGACUUGGCCCAAACCCCACUCUGAGAGAGGCCAGGCAGUGGGAGCAGACACCCCUGAACCUGCAGGGACUAGGGAGUCCUUCCUGAGACUCCUGAGGGUGCAGGUUGCAGAGAUGCCUGGGUCCUGCGCCUGGGAGGACAGCCACGGCUGCACCCAGGAGCUCCUGCCUCGCCCACUUGGAGGAGGCAGGGCUCUCACUUGUCUCCAGCUCCUGCCUGCUUCCUGGAGUGCGAGGCCCAGGUCUGCAGCUGCGGGUCUGGCAGCUUCAGCUGCACCCAGGAGGGCAGAUCCUGCCUCUUCUCAGUUCCCCCAAGAGCACAGGGAGGCUCGAAUCCACAGCUACAGGAGGACGGGGCUCCCACUAGCUCCAUGGAGUGUGCAGCCCCGGUGGCACCUCCCUGCUGCUGCUGACAUGAUGGCAUCAGCCACUGCCAUCAACAGGUGGGAUCCAGCACCUUCCCCUGGAGAGCAGGCAGUGCUGCCCAGGAAGGCAUCCUCCUCUUUACCUGAAAGAAUAUUUCUGUAACUGUGAUAAAACACACAUGAAAUACAUAUGAACUUUACCAUCUUAGCCGUUGAUAAAACACACAUGAAAUACAUAUGAACUUUACCGUCUUAGCUGUUGAUAAAACACACAUGAAAUACAUAUGAACUUUACCAUCUUAGCCGUUGAUGAAACACAUGAAAUACAUAUGAACUUUACCGUCUUAGCCGUUUUCAAGUGCACAGCUCAAUGGCAUUAAGUUGGACAACCAUCACCACCCUCCUCUCUAGAACUUCCUCCUCUUCCCAAACUGAAGCUCUGUCCCCAUGAGACACUCAUUCCCUGUCCCCCUCCCCAGCCCCUGGUACCCCCCAUCCUACUUUCUGUCUCUCUGAAUCUGACAACUCUAGGGACCUCCUAGGAGUGGAACCACACAGGCUUUGUCCUUCUGUGUCUGGCUUCUCUCACUGAGCAUAACGUGAUUGCAGUUGUUUUUUUUUUUUUUUUUUUUUUUUUUUGAGACAAGGUCUUGCUCUGUUGCACAGGUUGGAGUGCAGUGGCGCGAUCUUGGCUCACUGCAACCUCUGCCGCCCAAGCUCAAGCUAUUCUUGUGUCUCAGCCUCCCAAGUAGUUGGGAUUAUGGGCAUGUGCCACCAUACCCAGCCAAUUUUUGUAUUAUUAGUAGAGACGGGGUUUCACCAUGUUGGCCCAGGCUGGCUGUGAACUCCUGGGUUCAGGUGAUCCACCCACCUUGGCCUCCCAAAGUGCUGGGAUUACAGGUGUGAGCCACCACGUCCGCCCUCUGCAGUUUUAUUUAAGACAGAGUUUCGCUCUGUUGCCCAAGCUGAAGUGCAGUGGCACAAUCUCAGCUCACGCUGAGAUCCCACCUCCCGGGUUCAAGCGAUUCUCCUGCCUCAGCCUCCCAAGUAGCUGAGAUUACGGCACUCGCCACCAUGCCUGGCUAAUUUUUGUAUUUUUAGUAGAGACAGGGUUUCACCAUGUUGGCCAGGCUGGACUUGAACUCCUGGCCUCAAAGGCCAAAGUGCUGGGAUUAUAGGCACAUCCUGGAGUGGGAUUUUUAAAAUAUUUUAAAAAUUUUUUGUAGAAACUGGGUGUCACUGUGUUGCUCAGUCUGGUCUUGAACUCCUGGGCUCAAACAGAGUCUUCCCAGCUUGGCUUCCCAAAGGGCUGGGAUUACCAGUGUGAGCAAAGUCGGAAGAGUUUGUUUUUUUUUUCCAGGAUGCAACUGAAGAGGGAGAGGUGAAGGCAUAAGACAGGGGUGGACUGAAGCGAGUCCAUACAGGGCCCUUAAGGCUGGGAUUGAAAGCUCAGGGUGCCUCCUGUAUGCCUAUGGUUCAGGUGCUAGAAGUGGUUCUACAUCUUUUCUUUCUUUCUUUCUUUUUUUGAGAUGGAGUUUCACUCUUGUUGCCCAGGCUGGAGUGCAGUGGCGUGAUCUUGGUUCACUGCAACCUCUGCCUCCCAGGUUCAAGCAAUGCUCCUGCCUCAGCCUCCCGAGUAGCUGCAAUUACAGGCACCCGUCACCACGCUUGACUAAUUUUGUAUUUUUGGUAGAGACGGGGUUUCUCCAUAUUGGUCAGGCUGGUCUCGAACUCCCAACCUCAGGUGAUCCGCCUGCCUCGGCCUCCCAAAGUGCUGGGAUUACAGGUGUGAGCCACCGUGCCCAGCCAGUAACUUUUUUUUUUUUUUUUUGAAAUGGAGUCUUGCUUUGUCACCCAGGCUGGAUUGCCGUGGCACAAUCUCCGCUCACUGCAACCUCUGCCUCCCGGUUCAAGCGAUUCUCCUGCCUCAGCCUCCUGAGUAGCUGGGACUACAGGUACGUGCCACCACGAUUGGCUGAUUUUUGUAUUUGUAGUAGAGAUGGGGUUUCACUAUGUUGGCCAGGCUGGUCUUGAACUCCUGACCUUGUGAUUCACCUGCCUCAGCCUCCCAAAGUGCUAGGAUUACAGGCAUGCGUCACAGUGCCCAGCCAACUUUUACAUCUUACAGCAGAUACCAGCUUACGUGCUGUUUUAUACCAUGGAUUACCUGGAUAGCCAUUCAGGCCCUAAACACUCAUCAGCCCCUUCAUAUGUUGAAACAACAAAGCUUUUGCCAUAUUUCAGUGGGUCAAGGUUGUUGUAGCAGAUUCCUCUUUUUUUUUUUUUUUGAGAUGGAGUCUCGCUCUGUCGCCCAGGCUGGAGUGCAGUGGCGUGAUCUCGGCUCACUGCAAACUCCACCUCCUGGGUUCAUGCCAUUCUCAUGCCUCAGCCUCCCGAGUAGCUAGGACUACAGGCGCCCGCCAUCAUGCCCGGCUAAUUUUUUUGUAUUUUUAGUAGAGACGGGGUUUCACUGCGUUCGCCAGGAUGGUCUCGAUCUCCUGACGUCGUGAUCCACCCGCCUCGGCCUCUCAAAGUGCUGGGAUUACAGGUGUGAGCCACUGCGACUGGCUGCAGAUUCCUCUUCUUACAUUGUCCAUGCCUUGUAAUGUGUAACUCUGAGUCAUGGAAGCAAAGAGAACUAAUCUCUAAUAACUGUGAGUUUUGAGGAAGGUCCUGUUCCAUCCUGCUUUUUGUUGGGUAUUGCUUCUCAGUCUUCUGACUAUGGCAAUAGCAAAUGCUGUGACUGAUAUUAACUAGUUAGUCCUCACGACAACACACUUUGGAUAAAAUUCUUCUUUCCAUUGAACAGAUGAGGAGGCUGUGUCCUGGAUAGGUCAGCAAUAUACCUGCAGUCCCAUAACUUGCAAGUGGCAUAUCCAUGACAUCCAUUCAUUUUCAGAAUCAGCAGGGGGAGAUUCUCACAUGGGAAUGUCAGGCUCAGAGAUCCAGAGGUUAGAAUCACCAGUUCAAUAAGAAAUGGGCAAAAUGUUUCAUCCAGACCUGUGUGCUGGUCGUCCUUGUUGUGUUGAUGGUGGGCCUAGGGUCUGUAUGUCCCUCUGAUUUUAAGCCAAGGACAAGCACCCACAAGGCAGCUAGUAGAAACUGACUUAUGGACUUUGCACCUUGACCUUUCUCAACUUCCCUGGUGCCACCAACCUCACCCCUCCUCCCAUGAACGUGGGUGGCGAUGGACCCAUCUUGAGCAGAACUGCUGUGAUAUUCUAGGAAUUAGUAACCUUUGAGGACGUGUCCAUGGACUUCUCCCAGGAGGAGUGGGAGUUGCUGGAGCCUGCUCAGAAGAACCUGUACAGAGAGGUGAUGCUGGAGAACUACAGGAACGUGGUCUCCCUGGGUAAGGCAAGCAUCACUAAUUCCUGUGUUCAUUGAUUCACAUUUAUCUGGUGUAUUAGUCUGUUCUCACACUGCUAAUAAAGAAAUACCCAAGACUGGGUAAUUUGUAAAGGAAAGGGGGUUUAAUGGACUCAGUUCCACAUGGCCGGGGAGGGCUCACAAUCAUGGUGGAAGGCGAAUGAGGAACAAAGUCACAUCUUACGUGGCGGUAGGCAAGAGAGCUUGUGCAGGGGAACUCCCAUUUGUAAAACCGUCAGAUCUCGUGAGACUUAUUCAUUACCACGAGAACAGUAUGGGGAAAACCACCUCCGCCAUGAUUCAGUUAUCUCCCCCUGGCUCCACCCUUGACGUCGGGAUUAUUACAAUUCAAGGUGAGAUUUGGAUGGCAACACAGCCAAACCAUGUCAUCUAGCAUCUACUAUGUGUCUGGCACCAUGCUGGGAAUGGGGGAUUCAUUGAAGCCUUGAAGAACCAAUGUACUGAUGUGGGGAUUAAAGAGGGUCCACUUUCCCCAGCACAAACCUCACAAGUCACUAGUCUUUCCUCAUGGACGGGGUAUUUACUUUUUCAACCAGUGGCUUCUUCCCACUUGGAGCAAAGAGAAGCCCUGUGGAUAGAGGAAAAAGGAACUCCUCAAGCCUCCUGUUCAGAUUGGAUGACUGUACUAAGAAACCAAGACUCAACUUACAAGAAGGUGGCUUUGCAGGAGGAACCAGCCAGUGGUAUAAAUAUGAUAAAGCUUAUCAGAGAAGAUGGGGGAUGGAAGCAGUUAGAGGACAGCCAUGAAGACCCCCAGGGGCUUUUGAGCCAAAAGGCAUCCCUUCACGUAGUGGCCGUUCCUCAGGAGAAGGCUACUGCAUGGCAUGGAUUUGGGGAAAAUGGUAAUCUGAGCCCAGCCCUUGUUUUAUCACAGGGAAGCUCUAAAGGGAACCACUUGUGUGGCAGCGAGUUAGAUAUUACAAGCUUGGCAUCCGAUUCAGUCUUAAACCACCAUCAGCUGGGAUAUGCAGAUCGGAGACCUUGUGAAAGUAAUGAAUGUGGAAAUGCCAUCCGCCAGAACAGUCACUUUAUUCAACACGGGGGGAAGAUGUUUGUGUAUUUGGAAAAUGGGCAGUCAUUGAACCACGGUAUGGCCCUGACUAUCCACAACAAAAUCAACACGGCAGAGAAACCCUUUGAGUGCCACCAGUGUGGGAAGGUGUUCAACCGGAGGCAUUCUUUGAGCGAACAUCAAAGAAUUCACACGGGGGAGAAACCCUACGAGUGUCAGGAGUGUGGGCGAGCCUUUACGCACAGCUCCACCCUCACGCGCCAUCUGAGAACUCAUACUGGAGAGAAGCCCUACGGGUGCGGUGAGUGCGGGAAAGCCUUCAACAGGAUCUCAUCGCUGACUCAGCAUCAGAGGAUUCACACCGGGGAAAAGCCCUAUAAAUGUGAAGACUGUGGGAAAUCCUUCUGCCAGAGCUCUUACCUGAUCUUGCACAAGAGGACACACACCGGAGAGAAGCCCUACGAAUGCAGUGAAUGUGGAAAGGCCUUCAGUGACCGUUCCUCUCUCAACCAGCACGAGCGAACUCACACGGGCGAGAACCCCUAUGAAUGUAAGCAGUGUGGGAGAGCCUUCAGCCAGAGGUCUUCCCUUGUGAGGCACGAGAGAACUCACACUGGAGAGAAACCCUACAGGUGUCAGGAAUGUGGGAAAGCCUUCAGCCAGAGCUCAUCCCUUGUCACACAUCAGAAAACUCACAGCAGCCAGAAAACCUAUAAAAUCAUUGACUGUGGGAAAGCGUUCUACCAGAACAGACAUCUUAUUGGAUAUUAGCAAUUGCACGCUGCUUUGUAAGCCACUUUUUAGUACUCUGACACAUACAUGUGGUUAUCUUUUGCCCUGUUGUGAUGGAUAAUUUGAAAAGAAGUGGGUUUAUGUCACCUUCUCACCUUCUUAUAAGAAAGCUCUGAGAAUGGGCAUUUUUGUAUUUUGUUGUUGUUGUUGAGAUGGAGUCUGCCACCCAGGCUGGAGUCCAGUGGCGUGAUCAUACCUCACUGCAGCUUCAACUUCCUGGGCUCAAGUAAUCCUCCCACCCCAGCCUCCCAGGUAGCUAGUACUAUAGGUGUGCACCACCACGCCCAGCAAAUUUUUAAAUUUAUUAUAGAGUGGGAGGCAGGGUGCGGUGGCUCAUGCCUAUAAUCCUAACACUUUAGGAGGCCGAGGCGGGUGGAUCAUGAGGUCAGGAGAUCGAGACCAUCCUGGCUAACACAGUGAAACCCUGUCUCUACUAAAAAUACAAAAAAGUAGCCGGGCGUGGUGGUGGGCGCCUGUAGUCCCAACUACUCAGGAGGCUGAGGCAGGAGAAUGGUGUGAACCCGGGAGGUGGAGCUUGCAGUGAGCCGAGAUCGCACCACUGCACUCCAGCCUGGGAGACAGAGCGAGACUCCGUCUCAAAAAAAAAAAAAAAAUUAUAGAGUUGGGGUCUUGCUACAUUGCCAAGACUGGUCUUGAACUCCUGGGGUCAAGCAUCCUCCUGUCUUGGCCUCCCAAAGUGUUGGGAUUAGAAGCAUGAGCCGCUGUGCCCAGCCUGACGGGGCCUUUUAGUGGGAGGAGUUGCCAUUACACUACGUCCAGUAAGCUCCAGACUUUCGGAAAAGAUUGGUGGACGGGAAUGCUGUCAUGGAUGGGAUCUUGCCAAGAACCAUCACGUGUUAAUUUAGUUGCUUAAACAAAAGGUGUUCUGUUUCUUAACUACUUCUGUGUCUUUACUUUUUAUUUCAUUGUUCAUUGUUUUUAUUUUAAUAUUCUUUUCUGGGUUUAUAUGAGACGAGUUUUCACUCUGUUGCUGAGGCUGAAGUGCAGUGGCGUGAUCAUAGCUCCCUGUAGUCAGCCUUCAUCUCCUGGACUCAAGCAAUCCUCCCACCUCAGCCUCUCCGGUAGCUGGGACUACACAUGUGCACCGCUACCACACCCAGCUAAAUUUUUUUUUUGUAUUUUUGUAGUGAUGGGCUUUCACCAGGUUGCCCAGGCUGGUCUCAAACUCCUGAGCUCAAGCAAUCCACCCACCUUGGCCUCCCAAAGUGCUGGUAUUACAGGUGUGAGCCACCGUGCUGGUAUUACGGGUGUGAGCCACUGUGCUGGGAUUACGGGCGUGAGCUGCCCAUGCUGGGAUUACGGGUGUGAGCCACCGUGCUGGUAUUACGGGUGUGAGCCACCGUGCUGGGAUUACGGGCGUGAGCCACUGUGCUGGGAUUACGGGCGCGAGCCACUGUGCUGGGAUUACAGGUGUGAGCCACCCUGCUGGGAUUAUGGGUGCGAGCCGCCGUGCUGGGAUUACAGGUGUGAACCACUGCUCCUGGCCUUUAUUUCAGCAUUCUGUUUCAGUGUUUCACAUUGGCCACUUAGCUAGAUCCGUUUGUCUUCUGCAGUACUGUGCUGAUCCAGAGUAUAUGCUAAGACGGAAAGCGCUUUGGAGGUAAAGUUUAAAAAAUACAAGGGCUUCAAAAUAGUACUAGUAAUUUGAUCCAUUCACAAAAGGACAAAGGCUGGACAGAGACGUGAAGAAAUGAAUCAUUUACGCAAUGAUUGGGGUGUUCCAAUUAUGUGUGAUUUUGUGUUUUCUGCCGUUUCAUUUUGUAUUGCCAUAAUCAUUUUGACAAUGAAUACAAAUCAAAUAGCACCCAAAAUUGUGAAGGAUACGGAACCUCAUUGAUGAG